AAUAAAGAAAAUAGAUUCCAUGGAAUCAAUGAAUUGAUUUGCUUUACUAAAGAGAGAUCUUGACUGAUUGAAAUUUAACUGUUAAAUUAGAGUUUUUUUGUUAUGUAAAAUGAACUGUGUGAGGAAUCUAAACACUUAUUUUUUUGUUCUUUCUUUGUCGUUGAUAGAAGAAUAUUUCAGUCCUGAUAUUUGCUGUAACUAAUAAUUACUGGAUAAACAGAGAAGACACAUGGAGGAUAUUUUACCUGGGUCCAACAAAACCAUAGCAACAGCAGCAAGUUGAAAAGAGCAAAAAAAAAAAAAAGAGAGAGACCGAAGUACAAUUACAAUCCCAUCCCACAAAAAGGUCAAGGGCUACCUGAAAGACCGGUGGCCCCAGGAUCCUCAAAGCAUCCAAACCAUCCCUAUACUCUCAGAUUAAUAAUCCUUGAAUAUUUUAAUGGGAACAGAUAACCAGACUUGGGUGAGUGAAUUUAUUCUCCUCGGCCUGUCCAGUGACUGGGACACUCGGGUCUCCCUGUUUGUCCUGUUCUUGGUCAUGUAUGUGGUGACCGUGCUGGGGAACUGUCUCAUUGUCCUUCUGAUCAGACUGGACAGCCGACUCCACACUCCCAUGUAUUUCUUUCUCACCAACCUCUCCCUUGUCGAUGUCUCCUAUGCCACAAGUGUAGUCCCUCAGCUGCUGGCACAUUUUCUUGCAGAACAUAAAGCCAUCCCAUUCCAGAGCUGUGCAGCCCAGUUAUUUUUCUCCCUGGCCUUGGGUGGGAUUGAGUUUGUUCUCCUGGCGGUGAUGGCCUAUGACCGCUAUGUGGCUGUGUGUGAUGCCCUGCGAUACUCGGCCAUCAUGCAUGGAGGGCUGUGUGCUAGGUUGGCCAUCACAUCCUGGGUCAGUGGCUUCAUCAGCUCUCCUGUGCAGACUGCUAUCACCUUUCAGCUGCCCAUGUGCAGAAACAAGUUUAUUGAUCACAUAUCCUGUGAACUCCUAGCUGUGGUCAGGCUGGCUUGUGUGGACACCUCCUCCAAUGAGGUCACCAUCAUGGUGUCUAGCAUUGUUCUUCUGAUGACACCCUUCUGCCUGGUUCUUUUGUCCUACAUCCAGAUCAUCUCCACCAUCCUAAAGAUCCAGUCCAGAGAAGGAAGAAAGAAAGCUUUCCACACGUGUGCCUCUCACCUCACAGUGGUUGCCCUGUGCUAUGGUGUGGCCAUUUUCACUUACAUCCAGCCCCACUCCAGUCCCUCUGUCCUUCAGGAGAAGUUGUUCUCUGUCUUUUAUGCCAUUUUAACACCAAUGCUGAACCCCAUGAUUUACAGCCUAAGGAAUAAAGAGGUGAAGGGGGCCUGGCAGAAACUAUUAUGGAAAUUCUCUGGGUUAACAUCAAAGCUGGCAACUUGACUCAUGAGUAUGACUUAGAGAAAACAGCUUUGCCUCAGUGUUCUCCACCCAGCUGAGAUCUGACAGGUGUAAACUACAUUGCCCUGGCAACCAGGAAGGAGAUGACGUAGCAUGUACUGUGGAUGUUAUGGAGGAGGGGGAGUGGUUCAAUUGGAUGGGGUGUGGGACGUGGGGUUAUAUUUAUGAACAGUGGAGUUAGAUACUGCUGUUAUAAAACCUCCCACACUUCUUCCACCUCCACUCUUACAGCCUGACAAUCGUUGAAAAAAAAUUACUACUUACUGUUUUGAUUUGUCAUAUCGUUUGUAAUGAUAGACCUACUCAUGGAUCUUACCUUGGACCACUGGUACUUACACAUCCACAUUUUAUAAAAGGUUAUGGGGCUUCCAUUGAAAACAAAAUGCAUUUUUACAUUUGAAGACUCACUUUAAAUAAUUUGUAGUGUAUGUCAUCACAUGCAGUAAUUGUGUGAGUCAACAUUCUGAGAAAAGUGUUAUUGUCAAGGCUGACUAAAAUGUUUUUGUGCAGGACCUACAAAAGGUGAACAUAAUGUCUUCUCCUGAGUGCUGGAGCUAAUUCAGUGAAAAAAUAUCAACUCAAGGUCUUGUUUCACCUCGAUAGGGUGACAGUCAAUGGUUGUUUGUACUGAAGACAAUUAUUGACCAAGAAAAGUUAAGCUUCAGGUGCUUCUUGACAGUAUUCAAACAGUUUGAGAAGGAUUUUACUGCAUAUAUAGGUAUAUCGUUGAAAAUAUUAAAAAUGAUCAAUCUCUGAAAAAUCUGUAAGCUCUUUCUCAGAAUCUUCAGAAACACACAAAAAAGCACACAAAUUAUGAGAUACUGUGAAAAAUGUCAAAGACAUAGUUAAUUUAAGGAAAAACUCUUCAGCCAAAGUCAAUGAAGGGUAAGAUAAUUUAAUAUGAAGUUUGGAACGUCAAGGAAGGUCAGUCAACUAUGCAAAUGUUACCCUCAAGUCUUCACAUUGAGAACUUCUCUUGCCACCUCCGUCUUCGUCACCUUCACACACACAACAGAGCCAUAGGUGAAUUUUUGUAAAUCUUGUAACCUGGGCUUGUCUGAGAAUGGACUUCCCUUUGAAAAGGAGCAUAACUGAUGUAAAAGGAGAAGACAUAAUUGAAAAAGUGGAAAGAAAAGAAAGAAUAUGAUCAUAGCUGCUCUUCCUACUCCCUUGAAGGAGUCAGUCUUUUCUUCCUUUUGUGUCUUCUUUAAGUCAGUUGAUUUGCAGUUCUUACAUUUGUCAACACAUCAUCAUAGAAUCUAAGAGUUUUUACAGUGUUGAAGGCAUAUAACUCAAAGCCCAUUUGACAUCUGAAUUUUAUAUUAAUAGUAAUGCAAUCUUAAAUUUUGCAAGAUAGGCAGGCAUCCUAAAAGAUGACAAUGCUGGCAAAUUAAAUUUUUAUUUUAAGUAUUAUCAGUGGAGUAUCUAUUCUGUGUCAGUGUCAAUAAAUGGUUGUUGCACACAAUAGUCAAUAUGAUACCAUCAUAACAAGGAUAAUCUCACAUAGUAGGGAGGACAGAUGAUGAAACAAUGAUAAUGCAUUGUGGUAAGUGUUACAGUGAAGGGGAGCCCACUGGAAAUGAUUGCAGAAGGCUUCCUAUAAAAGGACCCUUGGAUUGAGACCAGAAAUGUAAGAACAAGUUAUCCAGAAGACAAGAAACCCAAAAAAGAAACAACCUGUACAAAGUUGUAGAGAUGUGAGCAAGCAUGAAAGUCCAAAAAAUGUUGGAAGUUCAAUUUCAGGGCAGAGAAGAGUGAGAGAGUAGUGAGGACGAAGCAGACGGGUUAGACACGGUCAGAUCCUGGAAGGCGUCGAAUGUCUAAGUAUCUUUUAACUUUAUUCUAAUAGAAAACAAUAGUCCGUCAAAAAUUUUUAGAAGGAGUAUAGAUUGAAAACAAUUACAUUUUAAAAGUAUCACUCUGGCAAAUGAGAUAGUGGAAGAAAAGAUUAGAGGCAAGAUGACCAGCCUGUCUGCUGGGUCUGCUUCAGUAAUACUCUUGAGACAUUCGAGACAUCUGAAUUAAGUUAGAUGCAAUUGGAAGGAGACAAGUAAAGUGGUGUCAUUUAAAAGUGAUGUCAGCUAAAACACUUCAUCUCCCAGAUUGGAAAUGCCAUCUGAAUAUCAUUCCUCUUCUAAAAUGUGAGGAUGCUGUCUGAACAUUCUGUAAAUUGUGUAGUAAACUGGAAAAUUCACCAUCGUGAACAUGCUCUAUAUGAAAUGGUAUGGGAAAGAGAUAAGAAGAAAGUAAUCAAAAAUACAAACAUACACAUAAUACAUCAAGGAGGAAAAUACGUGAAGAUGCUAUAUCUUCAUUUCUGCCAGCGGUCGUGUGGUCACGGUGUUCGUGACAUUUCUCCAUCAACCAUCACACAAUCCUUUGCCUUCAAACAACUCCUAAGCAUGUUGGGGUUCUUCCUGGAAGGGUUAUCCAAGUCUUGAUAUCUCAGGAAGCAGAAAUGCUGAGAGUGGGCAUUAGGUAUGUAGAAAUAGACUACUAUAGUCUCAUAUUCUGUAUUAGUCAGGUUUCUUUAGAGAGACAAGACUAAUAGGAUAGAUGAAUAUAUGAAAAGGAGUUUAUUAAGGAGUAUUGACUCACACGAUCAAAAGGUAAAGUACCACAAUAGGCCUUCUGUAAGCUGAGGAGCACAGAAGCCAGUUGGAGUUCCAAAACCUCAAAAGUAGGGAAGCCAACAGUGCAGCCCUCAGUCUGUGGCCAAAGGCCCGAGAGCCCCUGGUCAACCACUGGUGUAGGUCCAAGAGUCCGAAAGCUGAAGAAAUUGGAGUGGAGUCUGAUGUUUAAGGUCAGGAAGCAUCCAGCACAGGAGAAAGAUAGAGGCCAGAAGACUCAGGCAAUCUAGUCCUUCCAUGUUCCUCUGCCUGCUUUUAUCCUAGCCAUGCUGGCAGCUGAUUAGAUGGUGCCUACCCAGAUUGAGGAUGGGCCUGCCUCUCCUAGUCCACUGACUCAGAUGUUAAUCUCCUUUGGCAUCACCUCCAUAGACACACCCAGGAACAAUACUUUGUAACCUUCAAUCCAAUCAAGUUGAUGGUCAAUAUUAACCAUCAUAUAUUCCAUCUAUUAAAUUUCAAUUUUUAUCUUUUUUAUUUGAUAGAGUUUUUAAUUUCAAGGCUGCACUUUCUCGGUAACUUUAAUCUUCAUAAAUUAAAUUAGUUGGAUCACCUUAAGACUACACACACUUCUAAUUCAUAGCUGCUUGUGAAGGACAUUCCCAAUAGAAGGCAUGAACAUUGUCUUGAUACAGGAAUACAAAAUAAGAUGCUAUUCUAAACUUUAUUGUUUAUUUAGCCAUUAAAUAGAAAAAAUUUAAAAAGACACUGAAAAGUAUUUGAAAAUAAAAUAUUUUUCAUUAGUUAAUAACCAUAAAAACACCACUGAAGGUUUUCCUUAAAAAUCUAAU